GCACAAAUUCGCAGCAGGCGGCUGGGGCGGCGGCUGGGGCAGCGGCUGCAGCAGCGGCGGACGCUCUGCAUUACCCAGUCUUGCGUCCUCGGCAGGCGCCCGAAGCUGAGUGCGCAUCCUCUACCGCACCCAAGCUUCGUCUGUCUCGUCAAGCUCUUCAUGCUGCCCAACUAAAAGGAAAACAUGGGCACAGGGGAUUUUAUCUGCAUUUCCAUGACUGGAGGGGCGCCCUGGGGGUUCAGAUUGCAAGGUGGCAAGGAGCAGAAGCAGCCCUUACAAGUUGCAAAGAUUCGAAAUCAGAGCAAAGCCUCUGGGUCUGGGCUCUGUGAGGGAGAUGAAGUGGUUUCCAUCAAUGGCAACCCUUGUGCAGAUCUCACCUACCCUGAAGUCAUCAAGCUCAUGGAAAGCAUAACAGACUCUCUCCAAAUGCUCAUCAAAAGACCAUCCAGUGGAAUAAGUGAGGCUUUGAUAUCUGAAAAUGAAAACAAAAACCUCGAGCAUCUCACACAUGGGGGUUAUGUGGAAAGUACCACCCUGCAGAUUCGACCGGCCACAAAGACCCAGUGCACAGAAUUCUUCCUCGCCCCUGUCAAGACUGAAGUUCCCCUAGCUGAGAACCAAAGAAGUGGUCCCGACUGUGCAGGCAGCUUGAAAGAAGAAACAGGCCCGAGCUACCAAAGGGCUCCCCAAAUGCCUGACUCCCAAAGAGGACGCGUGGCAGAAGAGCUGAUCUUAAGGGAGAAGGUAGAAGCGGUACAGCCUGGGCCUGUGGUUGAGCUGCAACUGUCCCUUUCACAGGAGAGACAUAAGGGCGCUAGUGGCCCUUUAGUGGCUCUCCCGGGAGCUGAAAAAUCUAAGUCUCCUGACCCAGACCCUAACUUGUCACAUGACAGGAUUGUCCACAUAAAUUCGAUCCCUACUAAUGAGAAAGCAGACCCUUUCCUGAGGUCCAGCAAGAUAAUCCAGAUCUCCAGUGGCAGAGAGUUGAGAGUGAUCCAGGAAAGUGAAGCAGGAGAUGCGGGACUGCCCCGGGUGGAAGUGAUCCUCGACUGCUCUGACAGGCAGAAGACAGAAGGGUGCAGGCUUCAGGCAGGAAAGGAGUGUGUGGAUUCUCCAGUGGAAGGAGGGCAGUCAGAAGCACCUCCUUCUCUGGUAUCCUUUGCCGUCUCAUCAGAAGGCACAGAGCAGGGAGAAGAUCCACGCUCGGAAAAAGAUCACAGCAGACCUCACAAGCACCGAGCGCGGCAUGCACGGCUCAGGAGGAGUGAAAGCCUGUCAGAAAAACAAGUGAAGGAAGCAAAAUCUAAAUGCAAAAGCAUUGCCCUUCUUCUAACGGAUGCUCCCAACCCCAACUCCAAGGGGGUGUUGAUGUUUAAGAAGCGACGUCGGAGGGCCAGGAAAUACACCCUAGUUAGCUACGGUACUGGCGAGCUUGAGCGAGAGGCGGACGAGGAGGAAGAAGGUGACAAGGAGGAUACAUGUGAAGUAGCAUUUCUUGGUGCAAGCGAAUCAGAGGUGGAUGAAGAGUUAUUGUCUGACGUUGACGACAACACACAAGUUGUGAACUUUGACUGGGAUUCUGGACUGGUGGACAUUGAAAAGAAACUGAACAGAGGGGACAAGAUGGAGAUGUUACCAGACACCACAGGCAAGGGAGCCCUCAUGUUUGCCAAGAGGAGGGAGAGAAUGGAUCAGAUCACAGCCCAAAAAGAAGAGGACAAGGUAGGUGGAACGCCAAGCAGAGAACAAGAUGCUGCCCAGACCGAUGGCCUGAGAACCACGACUUCUUACCAAAGAAAGGAGGAAGAGUCGGUAAGAACGCAGAGCUCUGUGAGCAAAAGCUACAUCGAGGUGAGUCAUGGUCUUGGCCAUGUUCCCCAACAGAAUGGCUUCAGUGGGACAUCUGAGACAGCAAACAUCCAGAGGAUGGUCCCCAUGAAUAGAACGGCCAAACCCUUCCCAGGGUCUGUGAAUCAGCCAGCUACCCCCUUCUCGCCAACCCGAAACAUGACGAGUCCCAUUGCUGACUUUCCUGCACCUCCACCUUACUCUGCAGUCACUCCUCCCCCUGACGCCUUCUCCAGAGGGGUUUCAAGUCCGAUUGCUGGCCCAGCACAGCCCCCUCCAUGGCCCCAGCCUGCCCCGUGGUCCCAGCCAGCCUUUUACGAUUCGUCUGAGCGAAUAGCUUCCCGAGAUGAGAGGAUCUCAGUGCCAGCAAAAAGAACAGGAAUAUUGCAGGAGGCCAAAAGGAGAAGCACGACAAAACCCAUGUUUACUUUUAAAGAGCCCAAAGUAAGCCCAAAUCCUGAACUCUUGUCACUCCUUCAAAAUUCAGAAGGCAAACGGGGCACUGGAGCUGGAGGUGAUUCCGGACCGGAAGAAGACUACCUCAGCUUGGGGGCAGAGGCUUGUAAUUUCAUGCAAAGCUCCUCUGCCAAACAAAAGACCCCUCCUCCUGUUGCUCCAAAACCUGCAGUCAAGUCCUCAUCCUCCCAACCAGUAACUCCAGUUUCCCCAGUCUGGUCUCCAGGAGUGGCUCCCACCCAACCUCCUGCCUUCCCCACAUCCAACCCAUCAAAGGGCACCGUUGUCUCCUCCAUCAAAAUAGCCCAGCCUUCUUACCCUCCUGCCCGGCCUGCAAGUACUUUGAACGUGGCUGGUCCCUUCAAAGGACCACAAGCAGCAGUAGCCAGUCAGAAUUACACACCCAAACCAACAGUUUCCACACCAACAGUCAAUGCUGUUCAGCCUGGUGCAGUGGGACCAUCCAAUGAGCUUCCAGGAAUGAGUGGGAGAGGAGCUCAGCUCUUUGCUAAAAGGCAGUCGAGAAUGGAGAAGUAUGUGGUCGAUUCAGACACGGUGCAGGCCCACGCUGCUCGAGCUCAGUCUCCCACUCCAUCUCUCCCGGCCAGUUGGAAGUACUCCUCCAAUGUCCGAGCACCUCCUCCUGUGGCCUAUAAUCCUAUCCACUCGCCGUCUUACCCACUGGCUGCUCUCAAGUCUCAGCCAUCAGCUGCACAGCCCUCCAAAAUGGGCAAGAAAAAGGGAAAGAAACCCCUCAAUGCAUUAGAUGUCAUGAAGCACCAACCGUAUCAGCUCAAUGCAUCCUUGUUUACUUUCCAACCUCCAGAUGCAAAGGAUGGCCUCCCCCAGAAGUCAUCAGUCAAGGUCAAUUCAGCCCUGGCCAUGAAGCAAGCUCUUCCUCCCCGGCCAGUGAAUGCUGCCUCACCUACGAAUGUGCAGGCUUCGUCAGUGUACUCGGUACCAGCCUAUACCUCUCCUCCUUCCUUCUUUGCAGAGGCCUCCUCACCAGUCAGUGCAUCCCCAGUGCCUGUGGGCAUUCCCACCUCGCCAAAGCAAGAAUCAGCCUCAUCAUCUUAUUUUGUGGCACCAAGGCCAAAGUUCUCAGCCAAGAAAAGUGGUGUCACAAUUCAGGUGUGGAAACCAUCUGUUGUGGAAGAGUAAUCUUGUAGCUGAAGCUGAGUGUCCACUUUGCUUGAAAUGAAUUGUUUGCAGUGUUUCUUGAGUCCCUGAGAAUGCCUAGCAAAGUCCUCAACUUACUUAAUUUCAGAUAUGUCACCUCCUAAUCUGGGUCCAAGGAGUAUAAUAUUUUUAAUGAGUCAAAAAUCCAACUCAGAUUGACCUAAAAUAUAUUUAUCUUCUUUGCACACUUAAAAAAUCCAGGAGCACCCCAAAAUAGACAUGUACCGUUAUAUUAAGUAAGCAGGAGACUUAGGAUUUGUGCUGUAGCCACAAGAAAGACAGUGAUCAGUGAUAUCAAACAUCAGGAAUCAGCCUUUAUGUAACAUAACAGCUGUCCUCCUAUGGUGAAAGGUUCAAAUGUAGUGAAGGUAUAACCUAUAUUGACUGAGAUUUCCCUUUUAGGUAGUGCCUUAUCUCUAUUACUAGUGUUAAAGGAAUAAGGAAUCUAUGAAGGACAGGGAGCAGCUCUGGUCUGUCAAUCUCAGCCACCUGUUUGAUAUCACAGAGAAGAUACUCGGAGGAUUGUUGGAAUGUAUAUAGUUUAGUAAGAAGUGGGUAAGAAAGAGGGUCUUAAUUACUGAGCACUUAUUAUGUAUUAGGUUCUUUGCCAGAUGUUUUUACAUAUAUAAACUCAUUUCAGAAAACUUAUUUAAAGUAAAUGGGGCCGGGUAUGGUGGUUCAUGCCUGGAAUCCUAGCACUUUGGGAGGCUGAGGUAGGAGGACUGCUUGAGGCCGGGAGUUGGAGACCAGCCUGAGCAACAUAGUGAGACCCUGUCUCAAUAAUAAUAAUAAUAAUAGUAAUAAUGAAGUAAAUGGGAUAAGGAAAGAAGGAUAAUUAUCUUUAAAGGUUGAUUCCCACCCUCCCUCCCCAGUUACUUAAGGAACUAAGUGAGUACAUCUCCAGUUGCCCAUGAAAGCAUAAGUUUGUUUUCCUCAGCUGAGGCAAGUGGUAGAGUAUACAGGAUAACGAAGUAACAUGUAAAAGGCAGGACGCACAUAAAGGUGUACAUGGCUAUUGUUUCACCUGGAGAAACCACAUGAUUGGGACCUGAAGGUUUACUGACUGACUACAGGGGCUGAUUGUGAAGCACGAGGAACCCCAUGUGUGUGGAGACUGUAGGGUGAGAGCACACAAUUAUUAGCAUCAUUUCUGAGUGAUCUCACAGAUUUUUUUUCUUGUGUUUGCUUUGCUUUUUGACAACUGCUUCUCCCACGUUCCUUGCAAUUCUAUUCUCUCACCUUCACUUUACUAUUUGUAUUCGAUGGACCAGGAUAAUUCAGGCAAGGUUACCUUGUAAACUUUAAUUGGCCACACACCAUGUUGUCACCCAGCUGGCUAUGAAGUGAAUAAUGGUACUGAAAGUAAACCUGAAGACCUUUCUCAGAUCUAUUUUAAGUCUGAGUCUGACCAACCAUGGAAAAUAUUCGACAUGAAUUAAUGUAGAGAACUAUAAAGCAUUUAUGACAGCUCCAAGAAAAAUCAUCUACUCUAUGCAGGAGAUAUGUUUAGAGACCUCUCAGAAAAACUUGCCUGGUUUGAGGGUACACAGUACCAUUUUAAUCUUCUGAAAAUAUCUGUAUUCCUGCUCUUUUUCUGCUGUCACUGUCAAUCUGCUAUAUUUUUCACUAUCCUAUUAAAAUAUUACUGUCUCCUUUAUCUGUUCAAUGUCCAUAUUUUAAAAAAAUCUUCCUUGUAUGAGCUAUUCUGAUCUAAAUAAUUUCUCUGAUAUUUCUCUAUAUGGCUCCCACAACAAUUUCAUUGUUGUUAGCAUAUCUAUUUCUCCAUACAUUGUAAAACUGUAAUCCUUAGGUAUUUCUAAAACAUAAAGAGGAGAAUUAAGUCAGCUGCAGAACAAUGGGGCUGAUUCUUCUGCUUUUUCUCUGGAAAAUCUUUCAUUGCUUUUGGUGGAAAUUUACCUAGAGGUUACAACCACAGGAUGUAGCUUGGUCUCUUAUUUGCCUUUUUGGGAAACCAAUUAAGAUUAAUACAGGAUAAAGGAAAAAAGCAAUCUAUUCAUUAUAUAACACAGUUGUUUGUAUUACUUGUUCCCUGCAAAGGAAAUCUGUUGAAUGCUUGCAUUUUGAAUUCUUUUCUAAUAGAACAACCAAAAAAGGCUUCUUAUGGUGCAGCAGGAAAAAAGAUCAUUUUUAUAGCUUUGCAUUCUUAACAUAGCAUUUAAAGAGCGGCAUGAAUUAGAGGAAAGACAUGGAACACACAGGUAGUCGGUUUGAGAUCAUCGGCUUAAAAGUAUCCUAGGAUGGUAAUGACCCAGAAGUAUUUCCAGUUGUCUAGUGGUGUGGUAUGCAGGAAUGAGAAGUGUUUUCUUUCCAUUUCCUGUUGGACAGGUGGCAAUCUUAGCAGAGCCACUAUUUGGAGUUGAUAACUAAAGAUGCAAAUAACAUGACUAUGCCUUCUGGUCAUCCUAGGACUAUUUGGAGUUCUCCAAAACCUUGUAAGAGGCAUGUCAGGCAUGCAGUAAAAGCAUCUACAACUUCAGCUGGGCACUGGCAGCAUAGGUCUCAUCUUGGACCAUACAGUCCCACUUUAUAGAAGAGGGUGGAAGUUCUCCAAAACAAUAUCCACAACAAAGUCUGACCUCACUCUGAGGGAGAUGGGAAGUGGGAGGAAGAAGGACUAACCAGCUCCCUGGAGUAAGAGGAAUUUGCUUUCCCUGUCUGCCCACCAGGGGCUAUAUGUGCCACCUUUCAGGUUGGGGCCAAGGAAGUGAUGUCAGUGUGACAGAAGGGAGAGUUAGACCUCCAGACGUCAGCCUCCCUCCCAUGGGGUACAUUUUCAAUCUGAGUGUUGUUGCCUUAGCUGUGUUGGUAUUAGCUUGAUUGGUUGGUCCGCUGGUUAUGAGGUGUAGGGAGGCAGUUUUUGUUUAGUUUUUAGGACUUUGCCUCUUCCUUUGUCCUUAGCAUAAUUUCUAGGCAGAGCAUCCACGAAGUCGGUUUUCAUUGCCAGCUCAAGAGCGACAAUCAUUUACGAGUUCCUAUGUUAUGUUAGGUGCCUUAUGUAUAUUAUCCCAAAUCCACUGCAUGGUUUAAAUACAGGCACUGGAAUAUAAAUGAAAAAGGUCAUUACAGUCACUGACUUUCUGCAGGACCUUAAACAUUUCUCUUUCCACAAGUUUCCCCUUAAUCAUGUGUCAAACCUCUCUUCCUGACGGGAAUGUUGUGCUAUAAUGAAUCUGCAUAACGCUUGGGAUUCUAGGAGGAAGGAAGGUUCCAUGGACAUGUAAGUACAGCAUAUUCCCCUCAGUCUUCUAGGAGGGCAGAGUGAAUCCCAGAACUGGUAAGAUUGGGAAUCUGAGCAUUGCCACUUUAAUCUUAGAAUAUUUAUCAUUUUGACACAUCCUGUUUUUUAGAGAGGAAAACAAACACAGUUUCUGCAUUGGUAGUGUAAAGCAUACCUUGUUAGGAACGUGUUUUGUAAGACACAUUUGGGUUGUCACUCUAGAGCAUGUCAAACUUUGUACUUCAAAAUAUAUUUAGUAUGAUUGUUAGUGGUAACAUAUAUCAAGGCUUUGAAUUAACUGUUUUAUUUAAUUUUCACAAGAAGCACUUAUUUUAGCCAUAGGAAAACCAAUCUGAGCUACAAAUAGUUCUUUAAAAUAAGCCCAGGUUAUUUAGCUAUUCUAGAAAGUGCCGACUUCUUUCAAGAAGCAGGCAUUGUAGGACAGCUGAGAAUUAUCACAUAGCCUAAAUUCUAGCCUGGCAGCAAGAGUCACAUCUGAGAUGUCCAAAAAAAAAAAAAAAACACCUGAUCUACAUUGAAAGGGGGUAGACUAACGUAUGUGAGACCAUUUUCCUAUUUGCAGUUACAAGGUUAAAGAACUUUGAAGGUCAUUCGGCUGCUAAGAGGCAUGUCGAACACUCUGUGUGGCUCUUUCACAGUAAACCCUCCUAAGAGCAGAAGACACAUGGCUGUUAGUGUCUGCGUUUAGAUUUAAUUUCUCAAAUAAAGGCCCUUGGCUGCGUAUCAUUUCAUCCAGUUAUAAACUAGGGCUCCUGCAAGCACCCCCAUUCUAAGGGUGAAUUAUUGAAAUCAGUUGCUAUUUGAUGAGUCACAACUGGCCCAGCAGGCAGGGCAUUUGAAGUCAUGGUCAUCAAAAAGAAAUGAUUGUUUUUUGAAAAGCUAAAUGCUUAAAAUGCUUCUAGAGGGAAGUCGUGGGGCGUGUGCUCAUUCUCUUUAAAAUCAGGGUUGUUGAGUUUGUUUUUAAACAUUUUUAUAAGUUCAUGAGAAAAAAUAUAUAAAUUCUAAGAACCAACACUGUAUUCCCAGAAACAUGACCCUCGCUGGUCUUGGGUCCACAUAUCAUUGGACUCUGGGGGACACAAAGAUGCCUGUGACACUUUGGUGUUGCCGAGUUAGUCAACAAUUAUUCUGGGAAAAAGCAGAAUUGAAUUCUUCUCUAGAUGUCCUACCAGGGUUGGCCAAGGGCCACAAAGCAGGCUAAUAAAUUCCCACAGGAUCCAGACACCAGGCAAAAUUGCUCUAAGAAGCCAGUUACUGUCAUCCCUCUAUGGUUCUAGAAAAAAUAGUACAAAAAUGACAGGUCAUCCUAUGAGCGUCAUGCCAAUGAAACCCCAUCUUCUGGAGAAGCCCUUGAAUCAGAAUUAUCUUUUUUCUUGAUGUCGUCAGAUGCAGCCAGUUUCUUAAUUUUUUUAAAAACUGUAUGUUUCUGUGGUAUGUAUAUUUGUACACCUAACUACCUGGCACUUGGAAAUCACAGCACUACUCAGAGGCAAUUGAAUAAAGAGAAAUUUAAUUUUAAAUAUCAAGUCCUGUCAAACAUUUCUCAAACUUCUGAUUUUAUCAAAGGUUUGCCAGCCAAUAAAGUGCAUCCCAAGUAUACAGGGGAGAAAGCUAGACUCCUACAGGGUCCUAGAGUUUAAGUAAUUUUUUUGUUAUUAAUAUAGGUAAUAAUUUUUCUAAUUUUUAUUUUUUGGUUCCAAAUGUAAAGCUCCUUGUGUUUACCUCUGUUUAUGUCAUUCUUGACAUGUUUAUCUAAAUUAUGUGUGCUCUGUGACAGGUGAAAUGUAAAUCUGGGAUCCAUAGUCAAGAUAUCAUAAGGACCUACUUCCCAGCCUACCUUUCUUCCUCUACCUGAUAAUGAUAAUACUCAAAAUAACAACAUUCAAAGGAAACACAAAGAAAUCCUGCUUUCACAUCUCCUAUUUCUUGGGCUCCUUAAUAACUACUGAUGGUUUGUUCAUGAAAAAAAAUUUUUAAAUCAAAAGAUUGUACUUGGCCCUGAGUUGAAAAAAUUUCAAAAAUCAAAAGUUUGUACUUGGCCCUGAGUUGAAAAAAAAAAUUCACAUUCUAAGAAUAAACAGAAAAAUGUUCUUCUUGGAAGUAAAUAACAAAAGCCAUAGUGUUUUCAUUUGUCUUUUCUUCAGGAUACACGGUAGAAGUCAGAGAAUCUUUGAUACUUUUAUUUGGUGCAAUAAUCAAGGCCAUGCAACAACCCAAAAUCAAGCAUUUUGGUUCAAGUCAGGAUGACAUGAGUGGGGACAGAAGCUGUGGCAGUCAUUCAAAUAAUCUCAUGGGUCCUGAGGAAAAGACAGGAGUUAAUGUAUUAAGUUUCUACUAUAUGCAGGAACUGUGUUAAAUAUUUUACAUAAGUUUUGAUAAUAGCUAACAUUAGCUGAGCACAAAAUUUGGGCCCUGAUUUGUGCUGAGUAUCUUUCACAGAUUACUGCUUUUAAUCAGCAGUCCUUGUGAGCUAGGUAUGAUCAUUAUCCCCAUUUUAUAGAUUACAGAUGAGAUUCUGAGGCACAAAGAGGCUAAGUAACUUGCCAAAGAUCAUACGAUGUUAAGUAAUGGCCCCUGGAUUCAGUCUGCAGCCUGAAUUCUUAACCAAUUAUACUGUGAUUUCAUUAUUCUUCAGAAUUACACUAAAAAGAAGGUAUUAUUCCCAUUUUACAGAUGAGGUAUCUAAGCUCAGAGAAGCUAAACAACUUGUGCAACAAUCACUAAGCUUAUAAGCAGUGGAUUAGGGUUAGAUUUAGAUAUUUGUCUGGCAUCCAAACCUGUGCUCUCCCUACAGUACCACAUGGUUUCCACAGUCUCAUCAGACCCCGGAAUUUCACUCCCUGAGACUGCUUAAUUGUGAAUUUCCCAAACUGAUUCACCAAGAGCCUACUGUCUCUGCUUUGUAGAUAGCUUUGACCACAUUCAAUGACAUUAGGAAAGACUCCAUUUCCCAAGAUGGCUCAGAAAAUCAGAUGCUAUGACGCAUGUUGAAAGUGAAAACCCAUCUCUGAGAAAGAAGCAUCUGUUUUAUUAGUAAAAAAAAAAAAUGAAAUUUACAGCAAUGUUGUGUGACUUCUCAAAAUUCUUUCAUUUUCUUAUUUCAGAAUGAAUAGUGUUGUUCGUUGGCUGGGAAUGGGGAAGAAUGUGAUUUUUAAAAAUAAAGCAUAAUCAAACUCUGCAUAAAAGGAAGUGCUCCCUUUGGCUUUCUGCCAUUUUAACUAAAUGUAACUCAGGGAACUUUCUUAUUAAGUAGUGAAUCAGCACCUAGCAUGGCUUGCUACUAAACCAAUAAUAACUUAAGGCAUUUCAACAAGAAUAAUUCUAAACAGAAUAACGCUGAGGGAGUCACAAGUUUUCAGUAUUUCAGACUACACUCUGAAAAAGAGUUACCCCUGGAAUCUUAGAGUGUCACGGUGCCAAUCCCAGUCAGGACAGCAGUCAAGUGCAUGAGGCAGCAAACCCUUCCCACCUCAAAGAUUCCUCAGUGGAAGAUUUCUCAACAAUUAUUUCUGUCAAAGGCUUCCCAGCAAGGACACUUUUAAACCUUACAUUUUUUCCAGUGGUUUUUUUUUUUUCCUUUUAUAUAUCAUUGUUAUUUUGAAAACAUCUCCUGAGGAACUAGUGUGAUAGAUUCUAAACAUGGGUUUGGAACAGUCCCAUCACCAACUUCAAAAAAAGAAGAUGUGAGCUUCUAGGUUAAUUGUAAAAACUCAUUACAUUUGCAGAGCUUUAUUGACUUAAUUUAAAAUCAUAGAACCACUAAUAAGGUAACAAUUAUGGGGGCUUAAGAUGUGCUAGGUACCACUCUAAGCACUUUUUUGGUCACCACAAAAUGAUGAAAGUAUGAUGUAGGUACUAUUAUCAUCCCACUUUAAGAUGAGAAAAUUGAGGUAAAGAAAACUUAAGGAACUUGUGUAACAUGGUAGGGCUAAGCCUCGGGACCCAACAGUCAAACUCUAUGGCCAUCAUCUAAUCACAAGGCUAUACUACCUCCCCUGAUUGCAAGAAGACUCAGGUCACAGGUAAAAGGAACUGCUCAUCAGAAGUGAUGAGUUUUACAUGUCUCAGAGAUAACUCCAAAGUUACACUAAACCUUCUAAAUCAAAAUAAGAAAUAGUGCAACAUCUUAGAGUUUGGUAGCUCCAAGCAAUAGACAUUUUUAAACAGGGUGCAUGGGGAAAAGCUGUAGUUUUUAUCUCCAUCAGCCUAUUUGCUUAUUACAACUCAAUAAUGGCGAAGGGAAGCUCAACAUUUUGCUGGUUUCUGUUGAACAAAUUCCCACAGUGCACUAGACCACACGCCUCAAACACCUACCGCUUCCAGCCAACCAGCAUCACAUAUUACCAGAGUUAUGGUAAUUUAUACCUGGCAAAUAAAGGAAGAACAGAAUAGUGAUGAGAGAAACCCUCAAAUUUCAGUAACAAUAAUGCAGAGAAUAAGGUUCCUUCCAAUUUUUAAAUUAAAAAGAAGACAAGACUUUUUUUUAAUUUAGGAAAAGCAAAAGGUAAUCAUGUCUUAAAUGAACUUCACAUACUAUUAGAUGAGAUAAGGUGUGUAAACCUUGAGCCCACAAGAAGUACAUUGGUAGUGAUUAAGAGUGUGGGCUCUAGGGCCGCGCUGCCUGCCUCUGAGUCCCAGGCCUGCCUCCUGCUGGUUGGGAGACUUUAAACAAAGGAUUCAGUCGCCCUGUGCUUCAAUACCUCAGCUGUGAAACGAAGACAAUAAUAGGUGUACCUCACAAGUUGUUAUGAAGAUUAAAUGAAACAAUAUGCAUUUUGUAUAUAAAACACUGCCUGGCACAGAGAAAGUAUUCAACACAUGUUAGCUAUUAUUAUUCUUCUAAGGGGCACUCAAUAAACAAUAGCUACUAUUUUAAAAACUUCCAAUGAGGAAAACACAAUUAAACAAGUUCUUUUGUGUUCUCUGUUAAUAUGAAUCCCAGUUUGAGACCCACAACUAAAAUAGGAAAAGUAGAAGGAGUGUCGCUAUAAAUUUCACAUUGACACAAGAAAUCUAUUCCCAGGAGUCGUUGAGAGAUCUUUGUUUCUUCUCUUUUUUCUUCUUACUGAAGUUUAUAUGUUUACAUUCCUCUGUAUUCAGCCUGUUUGUCCAUUUUUUCCUGCUUUGUGUUCAUCUAUUGUGCCAGCAUUCUUUUCGUGGUAUACAAAGAUGAGAUCAGAUUCAAAAAGACUGGUUCAAUAUUUUUAUAAAAUAACAUCAGCUUUGAGCCUCUACUAUAAAGACACUGUUUUCAGUUCAAAGUACCAAUGUUAAAUAGAAUGAAUGUAGUGGACUUAGUAAUAUGAAGAGAGCUCUUCUGGGGAAAUGUUUGUAAACCAAACAUAUUCUCUAAACAGGAUAGUUGGUAUCCUGAGUAACCUGGUAGCAUAGUUGAAGCUUAAAUAGGCCUAUUACACUGAAAGUGGAGCAGUUGGCAACCCUAUCCCUGAGACUACCCCACUUCAGACCUGCAACAGUUGGGCUGACCUAGGAGGGCGCAGCUCACAGCUGUCCUUAUCCCUCCUUUCCACACUGUCCUAGGACAAAGGGUCAGCAACCUGGCCUUUUUAGAGUAAUUGAUCCCCUUGCCUGAGAGGCAUGAUCACUUUCCAAAAACAGAAAGAGUGAAACCUCGGCCUGAACAGAGCAAACUCCCAGCUCAGGGCAAGUGAUGAAAAACAAUUCUAAGAAGCUGAGCCACUGACAUAGGGAGGAACUUAAUAUUCCAGCUGCCUUUCAAACCCAGGGAAUUUUUGUGGGUUUUCUGGUACUUCUAGAAUCCUUCUGAGUCAGAAGCAGAAGUCAAGACUCAUCUUGAAGAUAAAAAAUCAAAACAAGCUGAGAUUCUGAAAAUGUUAUCUGAAUCCAGAAUAGCUUUUGUUUCAAAUGCAAUUGAAUUGAUUUAGUCUUGCUUUCCUUUUGUGCCAUUUAAUUACAUUUAAAAAUAAAGCAAAACUAGGCCUCUUACUGUACUAAAAACCCCUUUGUUCUUUUUUCACCUAGCAUAUCUAACACUGAUAAAGAAAUGUUCACAAAACCAUUUUCUAGAGCUAAGAAUCUCUAAGGAAUUGGUUGAACUAAUAUAAUGUACUAAUUUAAGGUUUCAUUGCAAUCCUUCCACAAUUAGAUCUUUGGUUUGGAGUUUUUUUUUUAAUUCACACUCAGAGUCUGUUGGUUGUGGUUGGAUUACUUAUUACUGUUUAACAAAUGGUGCAGAUCAUAAUUCUUCACGUAAGUCCAAUAUGGGCUAGAUUUUGAAUUCUGCAUUAUGAAAUACUCACUGAAAUGUCACAACUCAUUGUGGGUGGUAUUACUGAAAUAAACAGCAACACUAAAUAUAUUACUUAGAACUUUUAAUUUUAAUUUUACAUUGAAUGAACUAAUAUGAUUUCCUUUAUAUACAGCACUUUAGUAUGAGCAAACUAUUCCCUUCGUAGUGUAACAUAUAGCUUUCCACUUUUUGUUCCUAGUGUAAAAUUAAGAUUUCCCCACCUUAGAGAUAGCCCCACCUUAGAGAUUCUGAUUUACUAGGUUUGGGUGGGACCUAGGAAUUUGUUUUUGUAACAUACAACCCAGGUGAUUCUGAUGCUAAUGGGCUGUGAACUACACUUUGAAUAACACUUUUCUAACAUGCAAACCACUUAAAUCAACUUUAUUCUUUAAAACCCAUAAAUAGUUUUCCUGUUUAUCCAGUCAGGGACAGCCAGACUUGUAAACUGCACCUGCUUCCACAGUCUUAGUGCCCCGUCUAAAAGGAACAGGCAGGCGCUGAAGCACUCAUCUUGCCGAUUUUAUUUCAAACGUCCAGGAGAUGGCAGCAAACUCUCCUUCCCUCUCAGUGCUUCACAGGCAGCCAUUCUAAAGCUCGUUGCAUUACAAUUUGCUUUGAAUAUUCUUUUUUUAAAAAAGACAAAAGACUAAAGGGGGCCUUGAGACGUGAUUUUUAUCUGACCCCCUGCUUCUAAUCAAGAAUGAGUAUAAAUAUUUCUAGGGAUAGAAUAGAAUGAUACAAUUUUAUUAUCUAGAAAAGAGAUUGAAUUUCCUUGGCUAUUUUUUCUUAUCUCUGGGGAAAAAGAUUGUAUGACUUCCCUUGGCUGUUGGGCCCUAGACUCUGUUAUCUCCAAAUCCAAAAUAUUCUUACUAAUAACUAGCUUAAAUCUAUCUGGCAGUAAUCUAAACAUUCUUAUUUUGGGAUCUAGGCUAAUGGAAAAUUUUGAAGCACUUUGAAUGCUUAUUAGCUUUUUAAAAUGAAAAUAAAUACGAUUAUAAAAUUUUCAAAAGAAAAAGGAAGUUCAUGCACUUUAUGCAUCAUAGGGAAAGAGCCCAAUAUUUUUGUUUAACUUUAACAUUAAUCUUGGCAAAUAGAGUAGUAUGUCAACAAAAUGCAAAAUCAGUCAGAGGCUGCUUAUAUGUUACAAGAGUGUACGGAACAAAGAAACAGGCAGACCCACUUGGUGACGGCUUUGAUCCUAACAAGCACAUUGUUUUCAAAACUUUGAGGCACUAAAGUUUAUUUCUAAAACAGAAAAGAUGGUGACGUGUUGGAAGUUCUGUGAUGUGAAAUAUAUGUUUGUACAUUUACCAGUGGGAGGAGAAAAGACUAAUGGGAGAGCUGGAUAUUAUAAAUGAUGGGUUAAUGCUGGAGCCUAGGUCACUGCACAGGUUUGAUGCCAUGUGGUCAAUGAAUGACUGAUCUGUUCAUUGUAUUUUGUUUGUUUGGUUGGUUGUUUUUUUUCUUUUGUUUUUGUUUUGUUUUGUUUUGUUUUUAGACAGAGUCUCGCUCUGUCGCCCAGGCUAGAGUGCAGUGGCACCAUCUCGGCUUACUGCCAUGUUUUUUUUUGUUUUGUUUUUUGUUUUUGUUUUGGAUAAUUGCUUAAGAAUUUAGACACACAUACUACUAAAGGAUCUCUCUUUUCCUCUCUUUCUCUCAAAUGUGUAUUGAUGAGGGCCUAUCCAUUUUAGUCUCCCCAGAAGUUACUUUUUAUCUUAGGCUAAGAUUACAUAUCCAUAGCAGUUAAGAGGGCUGAUGUAGUAUUUUAGCUAAUUCAUAAUAUUUUUGUAAAUUCAUCAAUGCAUUUGCAUGAAUUAAUACUAAAAGUGAAAAAAUUGUUUAACAAUUGUAAUAGUCAAUAAAUACCUAACAUCAAAUCAAAAUGAAGGCAAACUUUGGGAUGGGGAGAAGUCAGGAGAAUACUAAAGAAUGAGAUCCUUUUAAUAAAUGUGUGGUCUACAUGGCAAAAUUUGCUGUAGUAUUAACAUACAAUGUUAUCUCAAGACAAUUAUACAUUGCAGCUUCAUGAAUGCAUUAAGAAAGCUAUGCCGGCCAGGCGCAGUGGCUCACGCCUGUAAUCCCAGCACUUUGGGAAGCUGAGGUGGGUGGAUCACUUGAGGUCAGGAGUUUAAGACCAGCCUGGUCGACAUGGUGAAACCCCACCUCUAUUAAAAACACAAAAAUUAGCUGGGCGUGGUGGCACAUGCCUGUAAUCCCAGGUACCCGGCAGGGUGAGGCAGGAGAAUUACUUGAACCUGGGGAGCAGAGGUUGCAGUGAGCCCAUAUCGUACUGCUGCAGUCCAGCCUGGGUGACAGAGACAGACUCCGUCUCAAAAAAAAAAAAAAAAAAAAAAAAAAAGCUAUGCAAAUAAAAACCAGCUGUAAUAGCAGCUAUAGCCAUGGG